AUUUUCGCGUCUCCUGACGAAGGGGCCCGACCGCGCCGCGUUUCGGGAGCGGACGUCCGAGCCACGGCCGAGGCCCGAUUAGUCCGUCCGGCACCGCUCGGGCACUUUCGGAAGGGAAGAGGUGGAGAACCGACGUUCGGGAGCAUUCGGCCUCGGGGACAUUCGGCUCGUCUCGGCUCGGCCUCGGGCUGACUCGGCUUCCGCCGGCGGCGGGAACGGGCGAAACCCGCGGCACUAAGCUCUCUCUGAGAGGCAGAAUUGCGCCGGCCGCCGGCGAGAAUCUGCCUAGAGCCGUCCAGCCCUGUCGGCCGGGGACGACAGCCGCCUCAGCCUGUCAGGACAGUGAGGAGAGCAGGGGCCGAGUCUCUCGGAAGCCCUCGUGAGGACUCGGACCUAUUCGGACUGAUUCGGCUUCCCACUUCGGGGAACUUCGACCCUCCUCGGUUCAGGACUCGGUCUCGGCUCGGCGGCUUCGUGCAGGUUCGGCUCCUACUCGGGCAGCCUCUGUUCGCCUCGGCUCCGCUCCGCGGGCGGACUCGGCUCGGCUCUGCUCGGCGGCUGGCUGCCUUUUCGGUCCCUAUUCGGGCGGCGGCUUCGGGCGGCCUCGGCCCAGCUCGGGCGUCCUCUUCGGGCCCCGCUUCGGGCUCCGCGACCGGCGCUUCGGGCGGUCCCGGACGGCGCCUUCGGGAAGGCUCGGCGGAGUCCGGAUGGAGGACUCGGACUCGGCGGCAAAGCAGCUGGGCCUGGCUGAGGCGGCGGCGGUGGCGGCCGCGGCCGCUGUGGCGGCGGCGGCCGCGGCCGCGGCAGGAGGCGAGGCGGAGGAGCCGGUGCUGAGCAGGGACGAGGACUCGGAGGAGGACGCAGACUCGGAGGCGGAGCGGGAGACGCCGCGGGUCACGGCAGUGGCGGUGAUGGCGGCGGAGCCCGGGCACAUGGACAUGGGCGCCGAGGCCCUGCCCGGCCCCGACGAGGCCGCCGCUGCCGCAGCCUUCGCAGAGGUGACCACAGUGACAGUGGCCAACGUGGGGGCUGCUGCAGACAAUGUCUUCACCACGUCUGUGGCGAACGCGGCAUCCAUCUCAGGACAUGUUCUGUCUGGUAGGACGGCCCUUCAGAUCGGGGACAGCCUGAACACCGAAAAAGCGACACUGAUUGUCGUCCACACAGAUGGGAGCAUCGUGGAGACCACCGGGCUGAAAGGCCCGGCAGCUCCCCUCACCCCAGGUCCUCAGUCUCCUCCAACCCCUCUGGCUCCCGGCCAAGAAAAAGGUGGAACUAAAUACAACUGGGACCCUUCUGUGUACGACAGUGAGCUGCCCGUACGGUGCCGGAACAUCAGCGGCACUCUGUACAAGAACAGGCUCGGCUCAGGAUGGGAUCUUAAACCCUCACGCUGCCUCUUGCACCUGUGCUGCCUGCUGCGACGACAUGACCUUAUCACCGUGACCCCCUCGGGACAGAUCACGACCUCGGGGGCACUGACCUUUGACCGAGCGUCCACGGUAGAGGCCACUGCUGUCAUAUCAGAGAGUCCGGCCCAGGGCGACGUCUUCGCAGGGGCCACAGUCCAAGAGGCCAGCGUGCAGCCCCCAUGCAGGGCCAGCCACCCUGAGCCUCACUACCCCGGCUAUCAGGACAGCUGCCAGAUCGCACCGUUUCCAGAAGCUGCGUUGCCAACGUCACAUCCCAAAAUAGUGUUGACAUCCCUGCCUGCGCUGGCGGUCCCACCCCCGACUCCCACCAAAGCGGCACCUCCCGCGUUGGUCAAUGGGCUGGAGCUGUCAGAGCCGCGGAGCUGGCUGUACCUAGAAGAGAUGGUCAACUCCUUGCUCAACACAGCGCAGCAGCUGAAGACGCUGUUUGAGCAAGCCAAGCAUGCCAGCACCUACCGAGAAGCUGCCACAAACCAGGCCAAGAUCCACGCUGACGCAGAGCGGAAGGAGGUGAUCCACCCGCCUCGGCUGCCCAAAGUCCUGGGAUUACAGCAGUCCUGCGUUAACUGCGGCCGGGAGGCUAUGAGCGAGUGCACCGGCUGCCACAAGGUCAACUACUGCUCCACCUUCUGCCAACGCAAGGACUGGAAGGAUCACCAGCACAUAUGCGGCCAGUCAGCAGCUGUCACCGUCCAGGCAGACGAAGUCCACGUGGCUGAAAGCGUGAUGGAGAAGGUGACCGUGUGAGGCUCCAUCGGCCGCCCUGGGAGCUGGGGCCCCUCGCACUCCUGUGAGGCUUUUGCAGGUCGAAGGCCCCCCUGAGGACUCUGGGGGGACGUUGAGAAGAGGGGUGUGGGAAGGUAAAGAAACUUGCUGGACAAGUCAUUAACACACUUUAAGCGAAUGGUGCCCUGGGAAGCGCACUCCCCCUGCCCGGGCCCCCUGCCCGCUCGCGGACAGAUUUUUUAUCCCUGGGAUCAUGAGCGUCCGGUCUUGCCCACAGGGCCUGUGCUGCGACGCACAUACAUACGUGUUGUGUCUGUCAAUAAAGUGUAAAUAAGGUCUCCCUGCCCCACA